GAUUUUGCUUGGACAUUGUGGAGAAGUGUUAGCCCCAAUGUGGACUGAUCUGGGAACAGUGGGAAAUUAACUUCUUGUUGGUAAAUAUCAGGCUGAGGUGAGAAAGCGACAUUUUCACCGUCCAUCUUUGCUGAUUUACCAUGCUCCCAGGAUGGUGGGAGUGUGUGUUUUUAAGAUGGAGAGUGUAUGCUUCUGGGUUCAAGUUCACAGGUGUCUCUGCUGGUUAUCUGCACUCACCUUGGUAACAGGGAGAAAGUGAGUGAAUGGAUUCCAAGAACUUACUGAUGGAAGUCUAAUUCAGGAGUUGGUUCUGCAGCCAUGGAGAAAUGGGCAGUGUCUGUCAGAGAAACCAACUGAUUCCUGAUAUUAUCACAAAGCCAGAUACUUGAAGAGCUCUAUUAAAAUAUGACUGAGGCCCUUUGAUGACCAGCCCAGCCUGUGGCAGAUACCCGCACUGAGGAAACUUGUUACUGGGUGUGCAGAUCAUGAUUCUGGAAGGAGGUGGUGUAAUGAAUCUCAACCCCGGCAACAACCUCCUUCACCAGCCGCCAGCCUGGACAGACAGCUACUCCACGUGCAAUGUUUCCAGUGGGUUUUUUGGAGGCCAGUGGCAUGAAAUUCAUCCUCAGUACUGGACCAAGUACCAGGUGUGGGAGUGGCUCCAGCACCUCCUGGACACCAACCAGCUGGAUGCCAAUUGUAUCCCUUUCCAAGAGUUCGACAUCAACGGCGAGCACCUCUGCAGCAUGAGUUUGCAGGAGUUCACCCGGGCGGCAGGGACGGCGGGGCAGCUCCUCUACAGCAACUUGCAGCAUCUGAAGUGGAACGGCCAGUGCAGUAGUGACCUGUUCCAGUCCACACACAAUGUCAUUGUCAAGACUGAACAAACUGAGCCUUCCAUCAUGAACACCUGGAAAGACGAGAACUAUUUAUAUGACACCAACUAUGGUAGCACAGUAGAUUUGUUGGACAGCAAAACUUUCUGCCGGGCUCAGAUCUCCAUGACAACCACCAGUCACCUUCCUGUUGCAGAGUCACCUGAUAUGAAAAAGGAGCAAGACCCCCCUGCCAAGUGCCACACCAAAAAGCACAACCCGAGAGGGACUCACUUAUGGGAAUUCAUCCGCGACAUCCUCUUGAACCCAGACAAGAACCCAGGAUUAAUAAAAUGGGAAGACCGAUCUGAGGGCGUCUUCAGGUUCUUGAAAUCAGAGGCAGUGGCUCAGCUAUGGGGUAAAAAGAAGAACAACAGCAGCAUGACCUAUGAAAAGCUCAGCCGAGCUAUGAGAUAUUACUACAAAAGAGAAAUUCUGGAGCGUGUGGAUGGACGAAGACUGGUAUAUAAAUUUGGGAAGAAUGCCCGAGGAUGGAGAGAAAAUGAAAACUGAAGCUGCCAAUACUUUGGACACAAACCAAAACACACACCAAAUAAUCAGAAACAAAGAACUCCUGGACGUAAAUAUUUCAAAGACUACUUUUCUCUGAUAUUUAUGUACCAUGAGGGGAACAAGAAACUACUUCUAACGGGAAGAAGAAACACUACGGUCGAUUAAAAAAAUUAUUUUGUUACUUCGAAGUAUGUCCUAUAUGGGGAAAAAACGUACACAGUUUUCUGUGAAAUAUGAUGCUGUAUGUGGUUGUGAUUUUUUUUCACCUCUAUUGUGAAUUCUUUUUCACUGCAAGAGUAACAGGAUUUGUAGCCUUGUGCUUCUUGCUAAGAGAAAGAAAAACAAAAUCAGAGGGCAUUAAAUGUUUUGUAUGUGACAUGAUUUAGAAAAAGGUGAUGCAUCCUCCUCACAUAAGCAUCCAUAUGGCUUCGUCAAGGGAGGUGAACAUUGUUGCUGAGUUAAAUUCCAGGGUCUCAGAUGGUUAGGACAAAGUGGAUGGAUGCCGGGAAGUUUAACCUGAGCCUUAGGAUCCAAUGAGUGGAGAAUGGGGACUUCCAAAACCCAAGGUUGGCUAUAAUCUCUGCAUAACCACAUGACUUGGAAUGCUUAAAUCAGCAAGAAGAAUAAUGGUGGGGUCUUUAUACUCAUUCAGGAAUGGUUUAUCUGAUGCCAGGGCUGUCUUCCUUUCUCCCCUUUGGAUGGUUGGUGAAAUACUUUAAUUGCCCUGUCUGCUCACUUCUAGCUAUUUAAGAGAGAACCCAGCUUGGUUCUUUUUUGCUCCAAGUGCUUAAAAAUAAGUUGGAAAAAGGAGACGGUGGUGUGGAAAUGGCUGAAGAGUUUGCUCUUGUAUCCCUAUAGUCCAAGGUUUCUCAAUCUGCACAAUUGACAUUUUUGGCCGGAGUGUUCUUUGUGGUGAGGGCUUUCCUGUGCAUUGUAAGAUGUUCAGCAGUAUCCACUCAUGGUCUCUAACCACUUGACACCAGAAACCCCCCAGCUGUGAUAACGCAAAAUGUCUCUAGACAUCACCAAAUGUUCCCUGGGGGUGGCAAAUUUGCCCUUGAUUGAGAACCACCAGUUUAGCUAGUCAAUAUGAGGAUGGUGGUUUAUUCUCAGAAGAAAAAGAUAUGUAAGGUCUUUUAGCUCCUUAGAGUGAAGCAAAAGCAAGACUUCAACCUCAACCUAUCUUUAUGUUUUAAAUGUUAGGGACAAUAAGUUGAAAUAGCUAGAGGAGCUUCUUUUCAGAACCCCAGAUGAGAGCCAAUGUCAGAUAAAGUAAGCAUAGUAAUGUAGCAGGAACUACAAUAGAAGACAUUUUCACUGGAAUUACAAAGCAGAAUUAAAAUUAUAUUGUAGAAGGAAACACCAAGAAAAGAAUUUCCAGGGAAAAUCCUCUUUGCAGGUAUUAAUUCUUAUAAUUUUUUGUCUUUUGGAUUAUCUGUUUACUGUCUCAUCUGAACUGAUCCCAGGUGAACGGUUUAUUGCCUAGAUUUGUACUCAGAGGAAUUUUUUUUGUUUUGUUUUGUCUUUUAAGAAAGGAAAGAAAGGAUGAAAAAAAUAAACAGAAAACUCAGCUCAGGCACAAUUGUCACCAAGGAGUUAAAAGCUUCUUCUUCAAUAGAGGAAUUGUUCUGGGGGUCCUGGAGACUUACCAUUGAGCCAUGCAAUCUGGGAAGCACAGGAAUAAGUAGACACUUUGAAAAUGGAUUUGAAUGUUCUCAUCCCUUUUGCAGCUUUUCUUUUUGGCUCUCUCAUGUCCUUGGCUUGCUCCUCUAUUCUACCUCUCUUUCUCCAGCAAUAAUAUGCAAAUGAAGACAUGUAUCCAUAAGAAGGAGUGCUCUUCAUCAACUAAUAGAGCACCUACCACAGUGUCAUACCUGGUAGAGGUGAGCAAUUCAUAUUCAAAGGUUGCAAAGUGUUUGUAAUAUAUUCAUGAGGCUGGAAGUAAGAAGAAUUAAAAAUUUGUCCUAAUUACAAUGAGAACCAUUCUAGGUAGUGAUCUUGGAGCACACAUGAAUAACUUUCUGAAGGUGCAACCAAAUCCAUUUUUAUUUCUGCCUGGCUUGGUCACUUCUGUAAAGGUUUAACUUAGUGUUGUCAAGUAACAGUUACUGAAAGAGCUGAGAAAAAGAACAAUGAACAGCAACGAUCUUGACUGUGCAACUCAGACAUUCCUGCAGAAAAGACAUAUGUUGCUUUACAAGAAGGCCAAAGAACUAUGGGGCCUUCCCAGCAUUUGACUGUUCAUUGCAUAGAAUGAAUUAAAUAUCCAGUUACUUGAAUGGGUAUAACGCAUGAAUAUUUGUGUGUCUGUGUGUGUGUCUGAGUUGUGUGAUUUUAUUAGGGGCAUCUGCCAAUUCUCUCACUGUGGUUCCUUCUCUGACUUUGCCUGUUCAUCAUCUAAGGAGGCUAGAUCCUUCGCUGACUUCACCAUUCCUCAAACCUGUAAGUUUCUCACUUCUUCCAAAUUGGCUUUGGCUCUUUCUGCAACCUUUCCAUUCAAGAGCAAUCUUUGCUAAGGAGUAAGUGAAUGUGAAGAGUACCAACUACAACAAUUCUACAGAUAAUUAGUGGAUUGUGUUGUUUGUUGAGAGUGAAGGUUUCUUGGCAUCUGGUGCCUGAUUAAGGCUUGAGUAUUAAGUUCUCAGCAUAUCUCUCUAUUGUCUUGACUUGAGUUUGCUGCAUUUUCUAUGUGCUGUUCGUGACUUGGAGAACUUAAAGUAAUCGAGCUAUGCCAACUUGGGGUGGUAACAGAGUACUUCCCACCACAGUGUUGAAAGGGAGAGCAAAGUCUUAUGGAUAAACCCUCCUUUCUUUUGGGGACACAUGGCUCUCACUUGAGAAGCUCACCUGUGCUGAAUGUCCACAUGGUCACUAAACAUGUUAUCCUUAAACCCCCCGUAUGCCUGAGUUGAAAGGGCUCUCUCUUAUUAGGUUUUCAUGGGAACAUGAGGCAGCAAAUCUAUUGCUAAGACUUUACCAGGCUCAAAUCAUCUGAGGCUGAUAGAUAUUUGACUUGGUAAGACUUAAGUAAGGCUCUGGCUCCCAGGGGCAUAAGCAACAGUUUCUUGAAUGUGCCAUCUGAGAAGGGAGACCCAGGUUGUGAGUUUUCCUUUGAACACAUUGGUCUUUUCUCAAAGUUCCUGCCUUGCUAGACUGUUAGCUCUUUGAGGACAGGGACUAUGUCUUAUCAAUCACUAUUAUUUUCCUGUUACCUAGCAUGGGACAAGUACACAACACAUAUUUGUUCAAUGAAUGAAUGAAUGUCUUCUAAAAGACUCCUCUGAUUGGGAGACCAUAUCUAUAAUUGGGAUGUGAAUCAUUUCUUCAGUGGAAUAAGAGCACAACGGCACAACCUUCAAGGACAUAUUAUCUACUAUGAACAUUUUACUGUGAGACUCUUUAUUUUGCCUUCUACUUGCGCUGAAAUGAAACCAAAACAGGCCGUUGGGUUCCACAAGUCAAUAUAUGUUGGAUGAGGAUUCUGUUGCCUUAUUGGGAACUGUGAGACUUAUCUGGUAUGAGAAGCCAGUAAUAAACCUUUGACCUGUUUUAACCAAUGAAGAUUAUGAAUAUGUUAAUAUGAUGUAAAUUGCUAUUUAAGUGUAAAGCAGUUCUAAGUUUUAGUAUUUGGGGGAUUGGUUUUUAUUAUUUUUUUCCUUUUUGAAAAAUACUGAGGGAUCUUUUGAUAAAGUUAGUAAUGCAUGUUAGAUUUUAGUUUUGCAAGCAUGUUGUUUUUCAAAUAUAUCAAGUAUAGAAAAAGGUAAAACAGUUAAGAAGGAAGGCAAUUAUAUUAUUCUUCUGUAGUUAAGCAAACACUUGUUGAGUGCCUGCUAUGUGCACGGCAUGGGCCCAUAUGUGUGAGGAGCUUGUCUAAUUAUGUAGGAAGCAAUAGAUCUCGGUAGUUACGUAUUGGGCAGAUACUUACUGUAUGAAUGAAAGAACAUCACAGUAAUCACAAUAUCAGAGCUGAAUUAUCCUCAGUGUAGCUUCUUGGAAUUCAGUUUCUGGAACUAGAGAUAGAGCAUUUAUUAAAAAAAACUCCUGUUGAGACUGUGUCUUAUGAACCUCUGAAACGUACAAGCCUUCACAAGUUUAACUAAAUUGGGAUUAAUCUUUCUGUAGUUAUCUGCAUAAUUCUUGUUUUUCUUUCCAUCUGGCUCCUGGGUUGACAAUUUGUGGAAACAACUCUAUUGCUACUAUUUAAAAAAAAUCAGAAAUCUUUCCCUUUAAGCUAUGUUAAAUUCAAACUAUUCCUGCUAUUCCUGUUUUGUCAAAGAAUUAUAUUUUUCAAAAUAUGUUUAUUUGUUUGAUGGGUCCCAGGAAACACUAAUAAAAACCACAGAGACCAGCCUGGAAA